AGUGGAAGAAACGCGGAACCAUGGCCGCUGUGGUUGCUGUUUGCGGUGGUCUAGGGAGGAAGAAGUUGACACACUUGGUAACGGCUGCUGUCAGCCUUACACAUCCCGGGACUCACACGGUGCUUUGGAGAAGAGGUUGUUCACAACAGGUAUCCAGCAAUGAGGACCUGCCCAUUUCAAUGGAAAAUCCUUAUAAAGAACCUCUUAAGAAAUGUAUCUUGUGUGGAAAGCAUGUAGAUUAUAAGAAUGUACAGCUUUUGUCCCAGUUUGUUUCUCCAUUUACUGGAUGCAUUUAUGGAAGGCACAUUACAGGUCUUUGUGGGAAGAAACAGAAAGAAAUCACAAAAGCAAUUAAGAGAGCUCAAAUAAUGGGGUUUAUGCCAGUUACAUACAAGGAUCCUGCAUAUCUCAAGGACCCUAAAGUUUGUAACAUCAGAUAUCGGGAAUAAAUUCUAUCACGUUACCACUAAUAAACUUAUUUUACAGUAAGUGGUUGUAUGAUGCCAAUACUGACUCAAACCAACCUUUGGAUAGAAAAGUGUUUGAGGAGUGAGGUAAAGAAUGACACUUCCCCUUCAUACCAAUGUCCAUUAAGCAGAUUGCUUAUUUAAAAUGUUAACACUCAUCACAUUUUAUCUAUGUUGAAUAAAAGUGGUUCUGUGUGAUUGUCAUUUAUAUCUGAUCCCCAAAUAGCUCAUACAAUAAUCCAUUCAAUAGAAUGGAAUUAAAACUGUUCAGAAUGAUUUUCCAACUAGCAAAUAUAAGUAUGCCUGGUUAAGAUAUCUUCCCUUUGUAGAAAUGUUACAUUGGGAUGGAUAGUGGUGCUGUCACAGAAGGACAAAAUAUUCCUAGACGAGUCUACCCUCAAACCAGUAGUGUCUUUUACAUGAAGAGAUGAUUUACACCUAAUAGACAUUGAAUAUGAUAGACAUACAUGUAUAUAUGUAUCAGUUCUGAGUUCCACUGGCCUAUCCCAAAUACACUGGAUUACCAGGCUUGUACUGUAUUCAAAAUGAUAGAUUUGCUAAAUUUCAUGCAAAGGACUCUAAACUAGGGGAGAGAUUACUGUUUGUGUUGUGUUAUAGUUGUGUAAUAAUUAAGGCUGCCAGAUUUAGCAAGUACAAAUGUAGGACAAAUUUAAAUUUUAGAUGAUGUUUUGCAAAUUUAUUGCAUGAUAUCCAGCAUUUUAUCUGGCAACUCUAGCCAUAAUGUACUUCUAAAAAAGUAUCACUUAAGGAGAAUUUUAAUGACUCAGAUAAAUUUUCAUAUAAAUUUCUUUCCAUAUUUUGAAAAUAAGGCUAUUCUUGCUUUUCCAUUUUAUUUUUUAAUAGACAUGGUCUCAAUACGUUGCCCAGGCUGGUCUCUAACUCCUAACUUCAAUCAAUCCUCCUGACUUGUCUUCCCUAAGUGCUGGGAUUACAGGUGUGAGCCACUGUGCCUGGUCUCACUUUUCCAAUUCUAAAGAAUGUGUCUGUGUAAGCCUUCCCCUCAACAACUUAGUGAAAGGUGAAAAAAAGGUUUGGAAAUAAAAGCAUCUGAUGUUUGAAAAA